AUUAAUCCCCUGGCCCAACCCGUCAUCUACUCUACCAUCUUUGCAGGCACACUCAUCACAGCGCUAAGCUCGCACUGAUUUUUUACCUGAGUAGGCCUAGAAAUAAACAUGCUAGCUUUUAUUCCAGUUCUAACCAAAAAAAUAAACCCUCGUUCCACAGAAGCUGCCAUCAAGUAUUUCCUCACGCAAGCAACCGCAUCCAUAAUCCUUCUAAUAGCUAUCCUCUUCAACAAUAUACUCUCCGGACAAUGAACCAUAACCAAUACUACCAAUCAAUACUCAUCAUUAAUAAUCAUAAUAGCUAUAGCAAUAAAACUAGGAAUAGCCCCCUUUCACUUCUGAGUCCCAGAGGUUACCCAAGGCACCCCUCUGACAUCCGGCCUGCUUCUUCUCACAUGACAAAAACUAGCCCCCAUCUCAAUCAUAUACCAAAUCUCUCCCUCACUAAACGUAAGCCUUCUCCUCACUCUCUCAAUCUUAUCCAUCAUAGCAGGCAGUUGAGGUGGAUUAAACCAAACCCAGCUACGCAAAAUCUUAGCAUACUCCUCAAUUACCCACAUAGGAUGAAUAAUAGCAGUUCUACCGUACAACCCUAACAUAACCAUUCUUAAUUUAACUAUUUAUAUUAUCCUAACUACUACCGCAUUCCUACUACUCAACUUAAACUCCAGCACCACGACCCUACUACUAUCUCGCACCUGAAACAAGCUAACAUGACUAACACCCUUAAUUCCAUCCACCCUCCUCUCCCUAGGAGGCCUGCCCCCGCUAACCGGCUUUUUGCCCAAAUGGGCCAUUAUCGAAGAAUUCACAAAAAACAAUAGCCUCAUCAUCCCCACCAUCAUAGCCACCAUCACCCUCCUUAACCUCUACUUCUACCUACGCCUAAUCUACUCCACCUCAAUCACACUACUCCCCAUAUCUAACAACGUAAAAAUAAAAUGACAGUUUGAACAUACAAAACCCACCCCAUUCCUCCCCACACUCAUCGCCCUUACCACGCUACUCCUACCUAUCUCCCCUUUUAUACUAAUAAUCUUAU